GAGGCCCAGAAGAAUGGCCAGUAACCGGCAAAGAUCACUCAGAGGGCCCAGUCACCCAUCUCAUAUGGAAGAACCUUUCCUGCAGAUGGUCCAGGCCAGCGAGUCCCUCCCACCCUCCCAAACGUGGGCUCAGCGUGAGUUCUUCCUCCCCAGCGAGUCCUGGGAGUUCCCUGGCUUCACCCGGCAAGCCUACCACCAGCUGGCUCUGAAGCUGCCGCCCUGCACAGAUAUGAAGUCCAAGGUGCGUCAGCGGCUCAUCCACCCUUGGAAGGGUGGCGCCCAGCACACCUGGGGCUUUCACACGUGGCUCGAUGUGUGCCGUCUGCCUGCCACCUUCCCCACCCAGCCUGACAGGCCCUACGAUAGCAAUGUCUGGCGCUGGCUGACCGACUCCAAUGCCCACAGAUGCCCCCCCACGGAGCACCCCAUCCCCCCUCCCUCCUGGAUGGGGCAAAACAGCUUCCUGACCUUCAUCCACUGUUAUCCCACGUUUGUGGACAUGAAAAGGAAGAAGCAGGUGAUUUUCAGGACAGUGAAGGAGUUGAAGGAGGUGGAGAAGCUCAAGUUGAGGAGUGAGGCAAGAGCACCCCCACUCGAUGCCCAGGGCAACAUCCAGCCGCCAGCGAGCUUCAAGAAGUACCGGCACAUAUCCGCUGGUGGGAGGUUUGAACCCCAGGGCCUCCAGCUCAUGCCCAACCCGUUUCCCAAUAAUUUCGCCAGGAGCUGGCCCUGCCCAAACCCUCUGCCUCACUACCAGGAGAAGGUGCUAAAGCUGGCCUUGCUGCCCAGCGCGCCCCUGAGCCAGGACCUCAUAAGGGAUUUCCAAACCCUGAUAAAGGACAGAACUGCCUUACCCCUCCACCAUCUCUCCAAGGCACAAGCAAGCAAAUCCCCAGCAAGGAAGAGGAAGAGAAGACCUGGACACUUCUAGAAGGGCUUCCAGAGGGGACGAUCGUGAUACCCAGAGCCCCAGGCUCCAGUGUUCUCAAUCAAUGCUCCUUCAGCAAGAGGCCCUGGGGUAGCAAAAGGACUCUGGCUUCUGCAGAACAGCCUCUCCACCAUCCUCCCAGCCUCAAGCCACCUCUGUACCCCAGGCUAUUGGAGAUUCAACUGAAAUUCUAAAUUGUUAUAUUUCUUCCUUGGAGGACUCUCAUCGAAGGGCCCCAUGCAGGGUUUGGAGGAGGAGAGGUCAGGUCAGGGCUGGUGCUGGAGAAUGGGAGAGUCAGGCCCCAGGAAGGCUAACCAGGUCUCAGCAGAGGAACAAGAGUAGAACAAAGUAGAACUUCAAGGUAAAAGAGCGGCCUCUCCACACCCUGUUGGGGAUACCUGUGGGGGAAGGGUGUGGAGGACUUAUGCCAAAAGAGCAGUCAGCCCAGAGGCCUUGGGCCUCAGCUUUUUCUAUCAGGGAGUCAAAGACCAGGGGUAAAGUAGAGGCAGGCAAAGCAACAGUCAGAAUGGUGUUGGCCCUGGCUGGGGUGGAGAUGGUUGGGGAGGGUGAUGGGAAGGUGGCUGGAGGGGAAGAAGCUGAAAUGGUGGGGGCCCUACCUCACCUCCUCCCACCCCCAUCACAUUCCCACAUUGAUGGUCACACCUGCUGGGCUUCUCUUGGCCUCCUGCCCACGGCCUUCUUUGUCUCCAUUUCUCUCAAGCCCUGCAGGCACCUGGGAAUCAAGACAUCACAGGGCUCUAGAGCUGCUUUAACCACUAAGCAGCAAUGUGACCUUUGGAAAAGUCACUAUUCCCUCUGGCUUUCAGGUUCCUCACCUGCACAAUGGGGACCAUUAGUUUAUAAAUAAAUGGAAUAAAUACAAGAAUAUAGGUGAAGGACCUGCAAAGUGUGUAGCACACUGGUGGCCCUCCAGAAAUGAAGCUGUCAAUCAGUGUUCAUAGAAUAAAAAUAAUAAGUAGAUAGAAUAUUAUGUAGCCAUAAAAAGAAAUUGAGUAUUGAUAGAUGCUACAGUGUGGAUGAAACUUGAAAACAUCAUGCUGAGUGAAAGAAGCCAGACACAAAAGGCCACACACAUAUUGUAUGAUUUCACCUACGUGAGGUACCUAGAAUAGGCAAACGUAUAGAGACAGAAAGUUGAAUAGAAGAUAUCAGGGGC